AUUGUGACUGCAGAGCUACUAUGGGGUGGGGGCAAAAAUAGGAAGUUUUGUUAACAUUGUGCCCAGGCUAUGUCUCUUAUGAAAUUGUGACACUUUCUUCAGAGAUUGCCCAUCUUUAUCAGAUGGAUCCCAAAUUAUUUCCACCACAAAAGGCGCUUGGCUACUUGUCCUGUCCAUGAGAUUUGUGUAAAGGGCCUACACACAGGUCAUUUCUUCUCAAAUCUCCACCAAUAAAACCUAUGCAUCACAUGUCCUCAGGGUCUUUAGAGGAUUUAGAAAUAAGUAUGCUAAAAUAAUUUCCCCAUACAGCACUUCCCUUUAUUAUGUUGACUUAUGUCAGACAAAAGGAGGUUUUUACUGAAAAUUUUGUGGGAGUCAAGGGAAUUCAAAGGGUCUCUCCUAGACGAUCCAGUGUUAUGUCCUCCACAGGACCUUUGGUGUUGGCCCCUCUUCCUCAUAUGUGAGGAUGGAUCCAGUGGCCUCCCCAUUAUCUCCUUUCUUUUCUUUCUGAACUCCAAUGUUUAUAAAGCCUGUACCCCUGUUGCCUAUGUAGGUUCUCUGACAAAAGUUAUACUUAGUGCUCUUUCUUUCUUAUGGGGAAAAAUCCGUGGAACUGAAGCUGAGAUCUUUAGUACGUGGAGUCACCUUACAGAUAUAGAGCAUUUAUGCGGUAUUCAUUGGUGCCUAAAGAACUUUAGGCAUCCUCUGGAAAACCGGCCCAGAGGCAGCGCAGACCAGGCACAAGCACGUUUCUUGGAGCAGGCUAAGUGUGAGUGUCAUUUCCUCAAUGGGACGGAGCGAGUGUGGAACCUGAUCAGAUACAUCUAUAACCAAGAGGAGUACGCGCGCUACAACAGUGACCUGGGGGAGUACCAGGCGGUGACGGAGCUGGGGCGGCCUGACGCUGAGUACUGGAACAGCCAGAAGGACCUCCUGGAGCGGAGGCGGGCCGAGGUGGACACCUACUGCAGAUACAACUACGGGGUUGUGGAGAGCUUCACAGUGCAGCGGCGAGUCCAACCUAAGGUGACUGUGUAUCCUUCAAAGACCCAGCCCCUGCAGCACCACAACCUCCUGGUCUGCUCUGUGAAUGGUUUCUAUCCAGGCAGCAUUGAAGUCAGGUGGUUCCGGAACGGCCAGGAAGAGAAGGCUGGGGUGGUGUCCACAGGCCUGAUCCAGAAUGGAGACUGGACCUUCCAGACCCUGGUGAUGCUGGAAACAGUUCCUCGGAGUGGAGAGGUUUACACCUGCCAAGUGGAGCAUCCAAGCAUGAUGAGCCCUCUCACGGUGCAAUGGAGUGCACGGUCUGAAUCUGCACAGAGCAAGAUGCUGAGUGGAGUCGGGGGCUUUGUGCUGGGCCUGCUCUUCCUUGGGACAGGGCUGUUCAUCUACUUCAGGAAUCAGAAAGGACACUCUGGACUUCAGCCAACAGGACUCUUGAGCUGAAGUGCAGAUGACCACAUUCAAGGAAGAACCUUCUGCCCCAGCUUUGCAAGAUGAAAAGCUUUCCCACUUGGCUCUUAUUCUUCCACAAGAGCUUUGUCAGGACCAGGUUGUUACUGGUUCAGCAACUCUGCAGAAAAUGUCCUCCCUUGUGGCUUCCUUAGCUCCUGUUCUUGGCCUGAAGCCUCACAGCUUUGAUGGCAGUGCCUCAUCUUCAACUUUUGUGCUUCCCUUUACCUAAACUGUCCUGCCUCCCGUGCAUCUGUACUCCCCUUGUGCCACACAUUGCAUUAUUAAAUGUUUCUCAAACAUGGAGUUAAAAA